AGGUGCAGCGGCCUCUUCCGUCAAGCCUUAGCACCUAUAAACUUUAUAAAACCUACUCUCUGUGAAUUGUGCAUGCCACUAAUCUUCAUCUAGCAAUACAUUUCUGCUCAUUCUUUAAAAUUCAUCUCAAGUACCAUUUGAUUUAGACGAGCCACCUCUUGGUUCCAGUGGCUUCCUGAUCAUACCUCUAGUGCUAUAUUGUAACCAUCACUUAAUUAGUUCAUGAUUUUUUCUCUUCUAGACUAUAAGUUACUUGAACAUAUGGAUUUGAGUCAGUAGGUAUAGGUGAGACAUGGGAAUCUGCAUGUUCAACAAAUUCCUCCUGGCAUUCUAGGGCUCCAAUCUCAGGUAUGUUUGUUUCUUUUUUUUAGACAAGAGUCUUGCUCUGUCUCCAGGCUGGAGUGCAGUGGCGCAAUCUUGGCUUGUCGCAACCUCCCGGGUUCAAGCAAUUUGCCUGCCUCAGCCUCCCAGGUAGCUGGGACUACAGGCGCACGCCAUCAUGCCCGGCUAAUUUUUAUGUUUUUAGUAGAGAUGGGGUGUCACCAUGUUGGCCAGGAUGGUCUUGAUUUACUGACCUCAUGAUCCACCCGCCUCAGCCUCCCAAAGUGCUGGGAUUACAGGCGUGAGCCACCGCGCCCGGCCUAACCUCAGUUUUAAGUGGUUUUUAAAAUCUACUUCAACUCUGAAAUAUCAAGGCUUUUCCUCCCUGCAAUUUAACUGGUAUUGGGGAGGGCAGGUAAAGCUUUCGGGUAGUUGAUUAAAAACAACAACAAAAAAAGCAGGGGCCGUCUUCUUUCGUGCCCACAAUAAGAGCUUAUACUGAAAUGUAGAGUAAGGUAGAUAAGUAGAAAUAAGAUAAAUACCCUUAUUUCAUUUAACAGUGUUUGCACAAUGUGUCCAAUUUUUAUUCACUAGUUCUAAAACUAUUGAGGGCUUACUAUAUGCCAGACACUGUUCUAGUCAUUGGGAGUACAUCAACACAGACAAAACCCCCUACCCUAUAGGAGUUUGCAUUGGUAGGCAAUAAGCAAAUAAAAUAAGUAAAGCAAAGUAUUUUAGAAGGUGAUAAGUAUUGUGGAGAAAAUAGAACAUUUAGGGGAGCUUUCUUUUAUUUGUCAGUGUUUAGUAAUAAAUUACUAGAGAGAGUAAUUUUUAAAAAUUUGAGCUAUUUAAAUAAGCCAUACUUUAAAAGGCAGGAUUUAACCUACAUCUAAUCAGAAGAGAACUUGGGAUUUGCAAAAUUCAGGUCUGGUUUCCUGUUAUAAAGUUGACAGUAAAUGGCUUUCCCAUUAUGUCAAUAGGAAUGAAAUAAUUUAGUGGCUCAGGGAAUUGCUUCCAAGGAGUCAAAAGUAAAUUGUGUUUAUAUAAUUUUUUUUACUACUAUUAAAAAAAGCCACAAACCAGAAAAAAAUUGUUUUGUACUUGUCUACAAGGCAGAGUUAAUUUUAUUAUUAAAAAAAAUCCUAUACUCUAAAACCUCUUCUAUUAUCUCCUCACUUCUUCGUUUUAAUUUUUUGUUUGCAUUUUCACGUUUAGGUAAAAAGAUAUUGGUCCUUUUAGGAUAUAUGGGGAUAGAAUUAUAUGAGGAAGCACAGGACUCCUGGUAUGGAAUGAGGAAGCUGGAGAUUUGAGCUUAACCUCUCUGGGGUGCUUAGAACUAAGUAAGAGAAGCAGUCUGUUUCUGCAGGGAAAAUCACUUCUCCAUCUUUACUCUCAAAUAACUUACUUAAUCAAAUGGUCUAAUGUUUCAUUGUAAAGAGUCUUAAAAGUCAAAAUUAAUGUCACCUGCAGAGUAAGCUAAACGAGUGAUGAGCUUUGUUUUGCACAGCAGUUGAAACUGAUUUUCAAAGUCCCACCAAACAGUAAAAGACUUUUCUUGCAUUUCUGAAAAACUAGAACUGUGUGGUGAUUCUGAAGACUGUCAGUUCCUGUGGGGUGUUUACACAAAGGUACUUUUAAAUGAAGAGUCAUUUUUAGAGCAAUUAGAGAAAAGGCUAGACAGAGAAGAGCGGCUCAGGGGCUUGGCAGGUCGGGGUUAAGGUUUAUUGACAGGACAGGGUCAGGCGUCUGCUUAGCCACCACUGCCCCGAGUACCUGCCCUCCGGAUACACCCAAGACCUCCCUGGCCUUGGCUCCCUGCCAUAGGCCAAACUCCCAUGCAGAAUGAGGAGAGGGGAAAGGAGGAAGAGGAGAGCAAGUUCUGCUGGUUCAGUAUUGAACUGCAAGUAUGAAAAUGUUUGUGUAUAUUUUUCUGGCCCAGAUGUUGUGUUAACAUUAGGAAGAAGAAACUUUAAAACAAAGAAUUGUCUGUUCUUUCAACUUUGUAGUUUGCAGUUUGCAUCCUGAAGAAAGAAAUUGCCUAGCUAAAGUAGUCUUUUAAUUUCAUUUUUUAGUUUUGAGUUACAGGUUUCUGGCAAGCUCCCUGACCACUACUGUUACCUGGUGGCGCCUAUAUUUCAUCAAAUUUAGACAUGCAGACUACCUGGAUCCAGGCCCAGAUGAACUGUUGUGACUGAUAAACAUGAUCCCACCCUGCCCCCAUGCAGACUCCUGCUUUUCCCUUUAAGGGAAUCUAAGACGUUGAGUCGCCGGAUCCCCAAGGGAGUUAAAGAAAAAUGUCUUCCGGCAUUCACAUUUGCUCUGUGGUUUUCUUGAGCUGCAUCUCUGCUUGCCCAGAGGCUGGUGAACAUCCCAGCAGUGCCCUGACUUCUCCAGUGUUGGUUCUCAUAGAAUUUUCUCUUCACCACUCAAUCAUAUCUACUUACACAAGCAGUCAAGCAGUCAACAAAGAAGAAAUUUCUUUUUUCGGAGACAAAGAGAUAUUUCACACAGUAUAGUUUUGCCGGCUGCAGUUUCUUCAGCUCAUCCGGUUCCUAAGCACAUAAAGAAGCCAGACUAUGUGACGACAGGCAUUGUACCAGACUGGGGAGACAGCAUAGAAGUUAAGAAUGAAGAUCAGAUUCAAGGGCUUCAUCAGGCUUGUCAGCUGGCCCGCCACGUCCUCCUCUUGGCUGGGAAGAGUUUAAAGGUUGACAUGACAACUGAAGAGAUAGAUGCUCUUGUUCAUCGGGAAAUCAUCAGUCAUAAUGCCUAUCCCUCACCUCUAGGCUAUGGAGGUUUUCCAAAAUCUGUUUGUACCUCUGUAAACAACGUGCUCUGUCAUGGUAUUCCUGACAGUCGACCUCUUCAGGAUGGAGAUAUUAUCAACAUUGAUGUCACAGUCUAUUACAAUGGCUACCAUGGAGACACCUCUGAAACAUUUUUGGUGGGCAAUGUGGACGAAUGUGGUAAAAAGUUAGUGGAGGUUGCCAGGAGGUGUAGAGAUGAAGCAAUUGCAGCUUGCAGAGCAGGGGCUCCCUUCUCUGUAAUUGGAAACACAAUCAGCCACAUAACUCAUCAGAAUGGUUUUCAAGUCUGUCCACAUUUUGUGGGACAUGGAAUAGGAUCUUACUUUCAUGGACAUCCAGAAAUUUGGCAUCAUGCAAACGACAGUGAUCUACCCAUGGAGGAGGGCAUGGCAUUCACUAUAGAGCCAAUCAUCACGGAGGGAUCCCCUGAAUUUAAAGUCCUGGAGGAUGCAUGGACUGUGGUCUCCCUAGACAAUCAAAGGUCGGCGCAGUUCGAGCACACGGUUCUGAUCACGUCGAGGGGCGCGCAGAUCCUGACCAAACUACCCCAUGAGGCCUGAGGAGCCGCCCGAAGGUCGCGGUGACCUGGUGCCUUUUUAAAUAAAUUGCUGAAAUUUGGCUGGAGAACUUUUAGAAGAAACAGGGAAAUGACCGGUGGUGCGGUAACCUGCGUGGCUCCUGAUAGCGUUUGGAAGAACGCGGGGGAGACUGAAGAGCAACUGGGAACUCGGAUCUGAAGCCCUGCUGGGGUCGCGCGGCUUUGGAAAAACAAAUCCUGGCCCUGGACUCGGUUUCCCAGCGCGGUCAACGCAUCUGGAGGGGACUGGAGGAAACCCCCUUGUUGGAAGAGAUUCCAAGAGAAGCACGGUUUUCUCUUUCCCUUGCCCUGACUGUUGGAGUAAAAAACCUCUUAAAUCCAUUGUAUCAGAGGUCCUUACCUCUCUGACAGUUACAGUGAUCUUUGUAUCUGAACUUUGCACGUCUGCCGAAAAAUCCGAACCUGUUGACUGGGAUUUUUAAGAAUCCGUUUCUCCCUUUUGUGUAUUCCAUAUUGGCCGGCCCCAAGGAUGCUCGCAGAAGCCAGCCCCCAACCCCAGCCCUUCCGUAUCUUUCCCCUCCAUCGCGGCUUUGCGAUGAAAGAUUAGCCCGCGAACAGAGGCAUUGAUUACAAACAUGUCCUUGGCAGUGGACUCUGGGCCUGGCCAUUCUUCAGGUUUCUGUCAAUCCAGAAACGCGACUUUCCUGGACCCCUGCGGCUCUUCCUCCCCCGCCCACAUCCAGCCCUCCAAGGCCAGUCCAGAGGUGAAGUUUGAGGCCCUCCCCCCACCCACCCCACACGCACGCACGCACGCUAGACCGUUUGCUGCACUAGGAAUUCGAGCUUGGGCCCCACUCGCCCAGGUGUGAACAGUGGCUGAUUAGUGGGCGGUCUAGUCUCUAAAAUGACCCCUCCCCAGACUGGCCCUUCUCGCAUCGGGACCCGCGCUUGCACGCUGCAGGAGCCGCAAACGUCAGCUGUUCUGGAAACCGAGAGGGUCCCAGAGAGAGGAGAUACGGGCGCAUUUGAGAGCAAGGGCCUACUUGGCCGGGACUGAAGCUUGCGAGUUGAGCUCCAGUUCGGCCGGCAGUUCCAUCCCGCUUCAGGAACAGGAAUCCAAGGGCCCACGCUCUGUCUGCCAAGGGCCAUUCCUGCCCGGAGCACCCUCCUUUCCCUUGCGCUUGCUCUCCGGUACCUGUUCCUCACCUGAGCUCAAGGGCAGGGAGAGGCCGGGCCUCUGGCAGUCCACGAAGGAAGCCGUCUGCCUUCGGUUAUGAUUUUAGGAACAAGUCCAACGAGGGUGUUCAAGCAGUUAAUGGUUGUGCUAACUCUUGUUUCUACUGAAGCGGGUUUUGCAAAGCUGACAUCCCUUAAAGAUAACUUGGGCUUUCGGAAGCGGCAAGGAAAUGGCACCUGUAGUUGCCAGGACAGGUGGUGUCCUCGGCCAGGACUAAGAGCCAGCUCAUCUUUGUAACAUUCAUAAUACGGGAAACUGAGGACCAGGUGGCUCGGAAAAGAGAUGAGUUCCAGCUUUUACCUAACACAGGGUUCUCUCGUCGUCCCCCAACCCCUCCAGCUCGGCUUCUUUGUGUCCAGGGUUGUAGAUUUUUGGAUAGAGGUGUUUCUGAUUCUAGUGAGUCUGAGAACUGGAAAAGACCAAGGAGGGGUUGAUGAUUUACAAGGUCCAUAGAAAAACUUUUUGUGUGGUCGGAAGUUGGCCAAGCAGAGGCCCACAGCCUGAUGCUACUGCCCCCCACCCCCCCAAAGAUCUGAAUUCCCUAAAGAUCAAGAGGGUUCAGCUGGCCUUGGGAGAUGUUUGCUGGAGAAUGACUUCAGUUUUCUCCUAAGGCAAUCAGAUUGCAACCAUUAGCAUUGUAUCUUAUCUGCAAAUCAGUUUACUCCGAGGUUCCCCAAGGAUAGUUUUAUUAGGACCACAGGACUUUACUAACCACUGAGGUAACACGCUGCUUGUGCAGCAAUUAUUUUGAGGUGGAGGUAUUUAUGGGACAAGUUUAUAAUUCCAUUUAUUAAAGGGACUAACCUAAA